GCAUGCGCGAGCGCCUAGCUGCGCGCAGCCACCCACGCGACCCCAGUCUGAGGUGCGGGGUCCUGGGGCCCGGCGCGGGUGGCCGCCGCGGCCCCUCGGGCUGCGUGGGGAGGGGGCUUCCGCCCCUGUUGUCAUUGCUCCUGCAGCCUUUUCGCUGGGACUGCGCGACACCGCCCCCCGACCGGGUGCCCGCUGUGUGCCAGGCCGGGUGCUGGGCACGGUCCCGCGAGUGCCCUAUAAGGACUGCCAGGCAAUAAUGAAGGUUCUUUUACUGAAGGAUGCGAAGGAAGAUGACUGUGGCCAGGAUCCGUAUAUCAGGGAAUUAGGAUUAUAUGGACUUGAAGCCACUUUGAUCCCUGUUUUAUCGUUUGAGUUUUUGUCUCUUCCCAGUUUCUCUGAGAAGCUUUCUCAUCCUGAAGAUUACGGGGGACUCAUUUUUACCAGCCCCAGAGCAGUGGAAGCAGCAGAGUUAUGUUUGGAGCAAAACAAUAAAACUGAAGUCUGGGAAAGGUCUCUGAAAGAAAAAUGGAAUGCCAAGUCAGUGUAUGUGGUUGGAAAUGCUACUGCUUCUCUAGUGAGUAAAAUUGGCCUGGAUACAGAAGGAGAAACCUGUGGAAAUGCAGAAAAGCUUGCAGAAUAUAUUUGUUCCAGGGAGUCCUCAGCACUGCCUCUUCUAUUUCCCUGUGGAAACCUCAAAAGAGAAAUCCUGCCAAAAGCGCUCAAGGACAAAGGGAUUGCCAUGGAAAGCAUAACUGUGUAUCAGACAGUUGCACACCCAGGAAUCCAAGGGAACCUGAACAGCUACUAUUCCCAGCAGGGGGUUCCAGCCAGCAUCACAUUUUUUAGUCCCUCUGGCCUCACAUACAGUCUCAAGCACAUUCAGGAGUUAUCUGGUGACAAUAUCGAUCAAAUUAAGAAACACCCUUGAACUGGCUCCAGAGGGACUGAGGAGAGGGUGCAGGAUGUGACCCAGAGCCCAAGGACAGACACUGCCACUCACUGCAGUCAGGAAGAGCAAAAGGCUUCACCUGCCUUCUCACAGGUGCAUCUCAUGUGGGGAGUAUGCACCGCUCUCCCAGUUUUAAAGAUGGAGCACGGGGCUCAGAGACAUCAUAUGGCCUGUCUGUAGGUCACACUGCUGAGAAGGAAGAGCUGCAGUUGAACCUGGGAAGACUGAUUCCACAUUGUCAGCCAUGGUGAUGCCUUGCCAUGGUCUCAGGAGCUGCUGAGCAGUUGAUGCACUUCUGGGCAGUAACUGAUACAAUUCUCACACCAGUCCAGUGGUGGGUAUCCAGAAAAAGAGGUCAGUGUUCCUCAUUACAGGUGAGGACACUGAGGGCUAGAGAGGUGAAACAACUUGCCAAAGUCAUGUUUUGAGUUCCUAGAAGGCCCAGGACUCACACAGGUCACCGAGGAAGAAAAACAAUAUCUGAAUCUUGUGGUUAGAAAGAUUAGAGAGAGGCCGGGCGCUGUGGCUCCCACCUGGAAUCCCAGCACUUUGGGAGGCCUCAGGCGGAUCACCUGAGGUCAGGUGUUCCAGACCAGCCUGUCCAAUAUGAUGAAAACCCCGUCUUUACUAAAAAUAUAAAAAUUAGCUGGGCAUGGUGGCAUGCGCCUAUAAUCCCAGCUACAUGGGAGGCUGAGACAGGAGAAUCGCUUGAACCCUGGAGACUGAGGUUGCAGUGAGCCGAGAUCGCGCCACGGCACUCCAGCCUGGGUGACAAGAGUGAAACUCCGUACCUGCCCCAUAAAAGAAAAAAAGAAAGAAAAAGAAAAAUUAAAGAGAUAGGACCCAUAAAGUGCUUAGCAUGGCAACUGGUCCAUAUGACCAGCGCUUACGUCAUAUUGCAGGUCAGGAUGGGUCACGGUGCUGGUCCUGCUCUGGUUCUUGUCCCUCUGUGCCCUGCUGCCUCUCCCCUGGGCCUGUAGGAGGAGUCCCCACCUCCACCCCACCCACCCACCCCCAAGUCACACAAUGCUGUGAGAUGCCUGGUGGUAUAAGCCUAACACAGUUUUCCCCAAGCUUCUUAGUGUUUGCCUAGAGGAAGAACAAAAGAUUUAUACUCUAUCUUCUUUCAAAGUGAGCAUAUUUAAAAGCACAAAUGGAUACUCAGCAUCUGAACCAAGAACUCAGGCCUUUCUGAAUAGACUGCUGCCUGCAUUGUCCACACCCAUGGCAGCUGGGGGCUGAGUGCGUGUUCCUAUCCUGUAUCUGUCACACCCAUUUCUGCAGCCCUCCAGACACUCUGAGGAGCUCUCAGUAGCCCCCUCGCCUCUUACUACAGUGAUUGAUUACCCUGCCUGCCAGUAGUUAACACCUCUGCCAUUGCUGAGGAGGAGAAAGUGACAGAGCUGGCCUUGCUCACAGUGACUAUGGACUGCUUGGGGGCCACGAAGGCACUGUGUGUGGGUUGUGAGUUGUCCCUCGACACUGGGACUUGGCGCUGGAUAGUGAGGUGCUUUCAAGGUUCACAGAGGACACAGUCCUAGCCCGUGAGUUGGUAGUUAGGCUUUUCUGUCUCAGCUCAGCCUCAGAUUUGCUACUGUCCUCCCUCCCCAGGAGUCCCUGUAGGGCCCACUGUUUGUACAGCAUUGCACAACAUGCAGGCGCACCACAAAAGAUCAAAGGGGGUGACUUCCGACCUGAACUUGCUACUUAUCCAUUGACUUGGGAAGACCACGCACUUGUCUAUAAAUGCCACAGAGAUGUCACUGCAAAGCAGUAGGUAAGCAGAUUCGUAAUCACCACCACCACACUAAUGGCAGCAGCUGAAUUUCCUGUGUACAGCAAAAUGCCCUUGCAGCCUGUGAGGUGGGUAUCUUCACACCUAGUGCUCACUAGCCACAGUGGCAGAGCCAGGCUGUGAACGUGGCUGCUGCCCCCAAAGCCAGGCUGGUGCACUCACGUCCAGUUUGUGCCAGGGAUGGAGAAAGAACGUUGAUGCUGGGCCCCCUCGCCUGGCCUGGGGAAGACUGCUGCUCUGUGGGGCAGCAUCAUGUGAGCAUUCAUUGACACAGGAGUGAAAGGCUCCUGUGAAAAAGCUGCUGUUUCACCAAACUGUUGAUACCCCUGCUCUAGGACUACAGUCAUGUUUGCCAUUUGCUGGUUCCCAGUCCCAGGGAGUUUCUUUUUUUCAAAUUUUUAAAUAGCUUUAUUGAGAUGUAAUUCACAAACCAUAAAAUUUACUUUUUAUGAUUUUAAUAUGUAAACUUAAAAAUUUUUUUUUUAUUUUUUUAGAGAUGGGGUCUCACUGUGUUGCCUAGGCUGAUCUCAAACUCCUGGCCUCAAGUAAUCUUCCCACCUUGGCCUCCCAAAAUGUAGGGAUUACAGGUGUGAGCCACCACGCCCAGCCCAAUAUGUAAACUUUAACAUGAUUUUUAUGAGAGUCACAGAUUUGUGCAACCAUCACCACUGUCUAGUUCCAGGACAUAUCAUCACCCCAAAGAGAAACCCGGUACCCAUUCGCAGCCACCCCUCAUUCCCUCAUUCCUCCCACUCCUUGGCAACCACUCAACUGUUUUUCAUCUCCAUGGAUUUACCUAUUCCGGACAUCUCAUAUUAAUAGAAUCAUACAGUAUGUGGUCUUUUGUAACUGACUCUUUUCACUAGCAUAGUGUUUUCAAGGUUCAUCCAUGCUGUAGCUGGUACCAGUACUUCAUCCCUUUUUAGUGCCAAAUAAUAGUACAUGCUGAGGACCGUUUUAUUUACCCAUUCACUAGUUGAUGGAUAUUUGGAUUGUUUUCCACUUUCAGGCUAUUAAAUAAUGCUAAACAUUCAAAUACAA